AUCCUGGACGAGCUCGAGCACCAAACGAAAUGCCAUCUCCAGCUCCUACAGCUCCACGGGAGGCUUGCCGGGGCUAAAGCAGAGGAGGGGGCCAGCCUCAUCCCGCUGCCAGCUGACCCUCAGUUACUCAAAGACAGUGAGUGAGGACAGGCCUCAGGCUGUCUCUUCGGGUCACACACGGUGUGAAAAGGGGGCAGAUACAGCACCAGGGCAGACAAUCGCCCCAACGGGUGGCUCCCCCAGAUCCCAGGACUCUAGGCCCCGUAGACGCAAGAUUCCCCUGCUGCCACGCAGGCGAGGGGAGCCUUUGAUGCUGCCACCUCCCUUAGAGCUGGGGUACCGGGUCACGGCUGAAGACCUGCACCUGGAAAAAGAGACGGCAUUCCAGCGCAUCAACAGUGCACUGCACGUUGAGGACAAGGCCAUCCCGGACUGCAGACCCUCACGGCCUUCCCACACUUUGUCCUCACUUGCAACAGGGGCUUCGGGUGGGCCUCCCGUUUCUAAAGCACCCACUAUGGAUGCACAGCAGGACAGACCCAAGUCCCAAGACUGCCUGGGCCUAGUGGCCCCCCUAGCAUCUGCUGCAGAGGUCCCCGCUACAGCUCCCGUGUCUGGGAAGAAGCACAGACCACCAGGACCCCUGUUCUCCUCCUCAGAUCCCCUUCCUGCCAACUCUUCCCACUCCCGGGACUCAGCCCAGGUCACCUCGAUGAUUCCUGCCCCCUUCACAGCUGCAAGCAGGGAUGCCGGCAUGAGAAGAACAAGGUCGGCUCCUGCAGCUGCCGCAGCAGCCCCUCCCCCCUCCACAUUGAACCCCACGUCGGGGUCACUACUCAAUGCAGUGGAUGGAGGCCCCUCACAUUUCUUGGCCUCAGCCACAGCUGCAGCACGUGCCCAGAGGUCAGAAGUGAGAUAUAACCAGAGAUCCCAGACCUCCCGGACCAGAUCGUGCCUCAAACGAAAUGCCAGCUCCAGCUCCCACAGCUCUACGGAAGGCCUCCAGGAAGUAAAGCGGAGGAGGGGGCCAGCCUCAUCCCACUGCCAGCUGGCCCUCAGUUCCUCAAACACAGUGAGUGAGGACGGACCUCAGGCUGUCUCUUCGGGUCACCGCUGUGAAAACAAGGCAGGUACAGCACCAGGGCAGACACUUGCCCCCAGGGGUGGCUCCCCCAGAUCCCAGGCCUCUAGGCCCCACAUCAACACUGCACUGCACGUUGAGGACAAGGCCAUCUCGGACUGCAGACCCUCACGGCCUUCCCACACUUUGUCCUCACUUGCAACAGGGGCUUCGGGUGGGCCUCCCGUUUCUAAAGCACCCACUAUGGAUGCACAGCAGGACAGACCCAAGUCCCAAGACUCCCUGGGCCUACUGGCCCCCCUAGCAUCUGCUGCAGAGGUCCCCUCUACAGCUCCCGUGUCUGGGAAGAAGCACAGACCACCAGGACCCCUGUUCUCCUCCUCAGAUCCCCUUCCUGCCACCUCUUACCACUCCCGGGACACAGCACAGGUCACCUCGCUGAUUCCUGCCACCUUCACAGCUGCAAGCAGGGAUGCCGGCAUGAGAAGAACAAGGUCGGCUCCUGCAGCUGCCACAGCAGCCCCUCCCCCCUCCACAUUGAACAACACGUCGGGGUCACUACUCAAUGCAGUGGAUGGAGGCCCCUCACAUUUCUUGGCCUCAGCCACAGCUGCAGCACGUGCCCAGAGGUCAGAAGUGAGAUAUAACCAGAGAUCCCAGACCUCCCGGACCAGAUCCUGCCUCAAACGAAAUGCCAGCUCCAGCUCCAGCUCCCACAGCUCUACGGAAGGCCUCCAGGAACUAAAGCGGAGGAGGGGGCCAGCCUCAUCCCACUGCCAGCUGGCCCACAGUUCCUCAAACACAGUGAGUGAGGACGGACCUCAGGCUGUCUCUUCGGGUCACCGCUGUGAAAACAAGGCAGGUACAGCACCAGGGCAGACACUCGCCCCCAGGGGAGGCUCCCCCAGAUCCCAGGCCUCUAGGCCCCACAUCAACAGUGCACUGUACGUUGAGGACAAGGCCAUCUCGGACUGCAGACCCUCACGGCCUUCCCACACUUUGUCCUCACUUGCAACAGGGGCUUCGGGUGGGCCUCCCGUUUCUAAAGCACCCACUAUGGACGCACAGCAGGACAGACCCAAGUCCCAAGACUGCCUGGGCCUAGUGGCCCCCCUAGCAUCUGCUGCAGAGGUCCCCUCUACAGCUCCCGUGUCUGGGAAGAAGCACAGACCACCAGGACCCCUGUUCUCCUCCUCAGAUCCCCUUCCUGCCACCUCUUCCCACUCCCGGGACUCAGCCCAGGUCACCUCGCUGAUUCCUGCCACCUUCACAGCUGCAAGCAGGGAUGCCGGCAUGAGAAGAACAAGGCCUGGCACCUCGGCUCCUGCAGCUGCCGCAGCAGCCCUUCCCCCCUCCACAUUGAACCCCACGUCGGGGUCGCUACUCAAUGCAGUGGAUGGAGGCCCCUCACAUUUCUUGGCCUCAGCCACAGCUGCAGCACGUGCCCAGAGGUCAGAAGUGAGAUAUAACCAGAGAUCCCAGACCUCCCGGACCAGAUCCUGCCUCAAACGAAAUGCCAGCUCCAGCUCCCACAGCUCUACGGAAGGCCUCCAGGAACUAAAGCGGAGGAGGGGGCCAGCCUCAUCCCACUGCCAGCUGGCCCACAGUUCCUCAAACACAGUGAGUGAGGACGGACCUCAGGCUGUCUCUUCGGGUCACCGCUGUGAAAACAAGGCAGGUACAGCACCAGGGCAGACACUCGCCCCCAGGGGUGGCUCCCCCAGAUCCCAGGCCUCUAGGCCCCGCAUCAACAGUGCACUGCACGUUGAGGACAAGGCCAUCUCGGACUGCAGACCCUCACGGCCUUCCCACACUUUGUCCUCACUUGCAACAGGGGCUUCGGGUGGGCCUCCCGUUUCUAAAGCACCCACUAUGGAUGCACAGCAGGACAGACCCAAGUCCCAAGACUGCCUGGGCCUACUGGCCCCCCUAGCAUCUGCUGCAGAGGUCUCCUCUACAGCUCCCGUGUCUGGGAAGAAGCACAGACCACCAGGACCCCUGUUCUCCUCCUCAGAUCCCCUUCCUGCCACCUCUUCCCACUCCGGGGACUCAGCCCAGGACACCUCGCUGAUUCCUGCCCCCUUCACACCUGCAAGCAGGGAUGCCGGCAUCAGAAGAAUGUUUCGUGUUCGAAAUUGUUUGAGGGGUUUGGGUUUAUUUUUGUUGGUUUUUUCUUUUUUUUUUUUGCUUACGUGGGCAUCCUUCAGCUUUUAAUAAUCUGAAAAAUUCUAUUUACCCAUUGUCAAUGUGUAUAAAUUAAUCUCAGUCAAUUUUAUACAAUAAAAGGUGAACUUUUAUCCAUCAAACAAUAAUUUAACAAAAAAUGUACCGGAAGAAGAAUGUUCAUUACAAAUAUAGGAAACAUAAAUAUUACCAAAUAUUGGCAAGCACUAAAAUGUUCAGAAAUAUAAGUCUAUUACAGUUAUAGCUCUCUCAAGCGAAAAAACAGCAGAGAAAAACUUAGUUUUCCUGAGGGGCUAUUUAUUUACUUAGGGAUUUGUUAAAAGGUCAAAUGGGGUCACACAGAAUACUAAGAAGAGCUGUUCACCCAGGCCUCACUAAGAACUCUUCUUCAUGCAGUAGCUAUAUAGUAAUAUGACAACUGCUCCUACGACCCAAAGAGGAACUACAGCAACUACUCUUUAGCAUCUGUUGCUCCCAACUCUGCUUUGCAAUUAUAUGACUCAAGCAUUCUGGCUCCGUUAACUAUUACUGCUGUUACUCCCAAGUAAAUUCCCUCUAAAAAAUAAAAAUUUUUAAAGCUGUAA